GGACAGCGGCGGAGAGGCGGACAGCGGCGGCGCGGCGGAGAGACGGACAGCGGCGGAGAGGCGGACAGAGGCGGAGAGGCGGACAGCGGCGGCGCGGCGGAGAGGCGGACAGCGGCGGAGAGGCGGACAGCGGCGGCGCGGCGGAGAGACGGACAGCGGCGGAGAGGCGGACAGCGGCGGAGAGGCGGACAGCGGCGGCGCGGCGGAGAGACGGACAGCGGCGGAGAGGCGGACAGCGGCGGCGAGGCGCGCAGCGGCGGCGCAGGCGCGGAGAGGCGCUGGCGCCGGCUCUGGCGCGGAGAGGCGCAGGCCCAGGCUCCACUCCCCAGCUGUGAAAGGGUGAAACAGAACCUACUGGAAUGAAGCUGGCCUCCCAUGGAAUGAAGCUGGCCUCCCGUCUCCUUGAUUUGAAGCAGCUUCUCCACGUUGGUUAUUAUGUCAUUUUUCUAAAUCUAACAUUUUAAAAUUUGUGCCUUUUCUUUCUCUUUUGCUUGACUUCUCAGAGGUUUUUUUAAUGGUCUUUUCAAAGAAGUGGUUUUGGGUUUUAUUUAUCAAGUCUACUUUUAUUAUGGCUGUUUUAAAAUUAAAUACAUUUAUUUCUUGUUUCCCUUAAAAAAGCUUCUUGUAUGUUUACUUAGUUUAUAUAAUUUUAUAUGUCUUCUGUUGAAGCAUAUUAACAAACACUUCCAGCUAUAACGUUUCCCCUGAGAACUGCUUUGGACACAUCCAGAGAUUUUGAUAGGUCACACACUUAUUGUAGUUUGUUUCUGAAAAGUUUUUCAUUUUAGUUUUUAUUUUCUCUUUUACUCAAAUUAUCAUCAGCUUUCUCCUUUUAUCCUGUUUCUGACAAAUUAAUCUGAGGAUAUAAAUUUCUCCCUAAAUGUCAAUUUUGUUGAGUUUCAUAAUUUUAAUAUGUAAUACCCUAUUGCUAUUGAGUUCCAGGCAUUUUAUAAUUUUCAUUGUGAAAACUAACUUUGUUUCCAAAACACACUUUUUCUUCUUUUUUGAGACAGAGUUUCACUCUGUCGCUCAGGCUGGAGUGCAGUAGCACAAUCUCAUCUCACUGCAACCUCUGCCUCCUAAGUUUAGGUGAUUUUGUUGCCUCAGCCUCCCUAGUAGCCGGGUUUACAGGCUUUUGCCACUAUGCCUGGCUAAUUUUUUGUAUUUUUAGUAGAGACAGGGUUUCGUCAUGUUGCCCAGGCUGGUCUCGAUCUCCUGACCUGGGGUGAUCCACCCGCUUCAGCCUCUCAAAGUGCUGCGAUUACAGGCAUGAGCCACCAUGCCCGGCCCCAAAAUGCACUUUUAACAUGGUCUUUGUUAUUGCAUGUUUCUAAUUUUGUUGCACCCUGGUGAGAGAAUGUGAUUUGUGUAACAGCAAUUCUUGGGAAAGGGGCUGAGGCUUCCUGCUCCUUUAGCACAGCUAAAUUUUCCCAAACGCCAUCCAUGAGCUUGGAAAGAGCAUUGUACUCUGUUGGGAUGGGCUCAAAUCUCUCUGUAAAAAUGAGUGUUCUUCUGUUGUUGUUGUUCUGUUUUUUGUUUGUUUUGUUUUGUUUGUUUUUUGUCUCAGUCGUUUUGUUUGCUCAGAUCUUUUGAUGAUCCAGAUGAUCUUUUAAUUUAUGCAGGAUGUUUCUCUGCUUGUGCAGGCUGGUGGGAUUGGGGACUGGAGAGAGGAUAAGUGUCUGCUUGCCCAGGACUGGCAAACUGUCACUUGCCCUGGUUGUGCCUUGCCAGGAGCUCCCGUGCCUGUCUCUGAGAGUGUCAUGAGCGCAGCGGUGGUAGUUGUGUGGUGGAUGCAUUUCCCCUGGGUUGGGGGGUGGGUGGCUGGUCCUAGCUCUGUUUGUUGUUGCCGAUGAGACACAGCACACUUCUGCUUCCUGAUGGAUCUUGUCGGUCAUUUGACUUCUUCCUGGUCUGGGCUCCUGAGCUGGCCCUCCGCAGGCCAAGCAGGAAUGGAGCUGGCUGCUACAAGAGUUCCUUCACUAGAGGGCAUCUCUCCUCUCUCCUCCCACACAUGGGAACACAAGGGUGGGCUUUCCUCCGCCCACUGUGAUCCGCAGCCCGGCUUUCCCCUCCUCACCCUCUGCUCUCAGACAGACUUGGUUUUCGCUGGUGUCUGUGAGAGGUGAUUCUUCAUGGUGCCAAGAAUGUGGAUUUUUUUGAGAGCAGGCACUCUCACAGAUAUUUGCACACCCAUGUUCAAAGCAGCGUGAUUCACAAGAGUCAAAAGGUAGAAGCAUUCUGAGGGUCUAUGGGUGAGUGGAUGGGCAAGCGAAAUGUGGUUAUGCAUACAGUAGACUGUUACUGAACCUUUACCAGGAAGGAGAUUCUUUUUUUUCUUUCUUUUUGUGGAAAAUGCAGUCUCGCUAUAUUGCCCAGGCAGGUCUCGAACUCCUGGGUUCAAGCUAUCUUCCUACCUCUGCCUCCCUAACAGCUAGGAUAAUAGGCGUGAGCCUAUAAUAUCACCCAGCCAGGAGGGAAAUUCUGAGAGGUGUGCCAACACACAUGAACCUUGAGGACAUUGUGCUAGAUGGAAUAAGCCAGCCACAAAAGGACAAAUACAUUGCGAUUUCACUUACAUGAGGGGCCCAGAAUGGGCAAAUUCAAAUACAGAAAGAGCAAUGGUUAACAAAAGGAGGGAGUUGGUGUUCAAUGGGUCUGGUUUCCUUUUGGGAAGAUGAAGACGUUCUGGAGAUGGACGGUGGUAGGGGAUAUGCGACAAUGUGAGUGCACUUAAUGCCAGUUAUAACACGGGGAGCGCGUGUGCACACGGCUCUGGGAGUUCUCGUGCAGCACUCAGAGCUCAGCGUGGGCGAGGGCGUCACCCCUCUGGGGGCGUCCAUGGGGCCUUGGAGAAGGGAGGCUUCAGGGCACCAGAGCAGUCUACCGGGAGAGGCCGGGCCGAGCGCUUGUUCACCCCCAGCCCUCUUAGGGAACUUUCACAUGCUUCUCCCACUAGGCCUAGGCACCCCUCCCUACUCUCCCUACCCUCCUGGUUCCCUGACCCUCAGUGACUGUGUCCUUCAAGACUGAACUCCAGAGUCCCCACCCGAGGACCCGCAGUGCCCAGCCCCCGCGAGCUCGCGGGGUGUAUGCCCACCCCGAGGCUCCACCGCGCCUGUGUGCUGGGAAGCCUGGCUCCAUGGGACCCUCGGGCUCUGGGCGCGCUGUCGCUGCAGCUGCCAGCAGCUCCUGAGGAAGUGGCUCGAGGCCCUGGGGCGGGCCAGGCGUGCGGUGGGCCCGCAGCCCUCACACCGGCCCCGGCCGCACACAGGAGGCACAAUCAGCAGAGACGUUGGACAGGGUUGGACACUGGCUGUCUCUUUCGGGCCUCAGUUUUCACGUCUGAAAUAAAAGCGAGCAUCCUGGCCCUGGCGCCAUGCCUCUGCCGCGGUAGAGGUUUCCACCCCUAUGAGCCCAGUGCGCCUUCCAGGCUCGAGGGAGAGGGAGUGUGCGUGCGUGUGAACGCGUCACACUCUUGUGUGAACGCGUCAUACGCUUGUGAAAGACUGUGCGUGUGCACACGCGUGUACGUGCAUGUGAACGCAUCAGGGUGCCCGAGGAUGCACACAUGCACGUGUGAGUGUGCGCGAGUGCGUGCUCAGAGGACAGCUCUCAGCAGGCUGGGGACCUCCUUCCUCUCACCCCUGAGGGUUUUGGGGGACCAGCCCCCGUCUCCGGGUGCUAUGGGAUGCCCUGGGGCGAGCUCCCACCGCUGUGCUCGGGCUCCGGCUUUGUGGGGACCCGGCCUUCCCCGCCCUCACCACGGGGAGUUCCACGCAGCACCCACGAGGUGGCGCCGCAGACUCGCUAUCGCGGAGCGUGGCGGCUCCCAGCAGCCUUGCCUACAGCUGUGGCCAGGGCGAUCCCUCUCAGGCCCAGGCCGCUGCUGCCAGGAAGAGCAGGAACAAUAGCCAGUCACGCCUGGUGAUGCCCUGAAGUGCUUAUGCUCCCAGGCAUGGGCUGUCCACAACGUGCAUUCUCUCCUUUUAUGCCCCUACUAUUUGGAACGCUGUAUUUUUUCAUUUUUAUUUUUAUUUUUUGUUGUAAAUCUGCCACUUAAAAAUACCCAGGGUGGAGCUAAAAGUACAGACACUGCUCAACUUACCCCUGGCUGCGGCCCAAUAAGGCCGCUGCGAGUGGAAAAUGACUGAGUCCACCUGACUACCGAAUAGCACAGCGUGGGGGGGCCCACCUUGGCCUGCUGAGAACACUGCCCUGAGCCUGCGGUGGGCAGAAGCAUCAACACGAAGCCUGUUUUGUAGUCAAGUGUCGGAUACCUCAUGUAAUCAUUGACUGCUGUACUGAAAGUGAAAAACUGGCCGUGUGGGACUCACACGAGGGUUUCUGCUGACUGUGGAUGGCUUUUGCAUCACUAUAAAGUUGAAAACUGUUAAGUGGAACUGCGGUAAGUCGGGGCUGUGUGCGCUAGAGACCUGAGUUCUGCCGCUCCAUAGCUGUGUGACUUUGGACACAUAUUUGAGCCUGAGUGUCUUCUACACAAAAUGGAUUUCUUAGCAUAACCUACACAUGUGUACGUGCCCGUGAGCGUGCACGUGUGUGUUUGCAUGAACACAUCUGUGUAUGCACGAAUGUGUGCACAUUUGUGUGUGUCUGUGUAAGUCCGUAUGUACAUUUGUGUGCAUGUCUGUGUGUGCAUAUGUUUGUAUGUGUGUGUGCUAUGCAUGUGUGUGUUAAGGCCCUGGGGUGGAGCUGAGGAGUUGAGGGGAGAUGCUGGGAGGGCAGCCAGCACCAGGCGUUUGUUGGCCAGGAGAGAAGCUGCCAUCCAGGUGCACUCUGGAGCUCGUGCUUCAGUGGCACAAUGCUUUGGGAGUGAGGAAGCUGGGGGCUGGGGCAGGGCAGUCCUGCACCUCAGGGGAGGUGCAGAGUGAGGCCAGGAGGAUGGAAAGAGUGCCAGAGAAUGGGGGAAAUCUGAGGCAUCAGGAAAGGAAGACACAGGCCAUGGAGAGGGCAGCUGGGCCCUGGGUGAGGCCGGCCCUCAGGAAGGAGGUGCCACAGGCAGGGGAGUGCCCAGAUGGAGAGCCCAGGGGUAUGGACCCACGGGUGUAUGACAGUGGGGGUACUCCUGAAACAGAGCAGUGUUAUCCAACAAGCAGGGUUGGGACAACUAGUUAUUUCAUUUAAAAAAACAGGUCAAUGUCAGUCCUCAUACUGUGCUUUAAAAUAAGCUCCAGAUGGACUCAUGUUUUACAUGUAAAGAAAAGAAGGCAAAAAGAAAAUAAAGAAAAGGCUUGUAAGCAGGUAGUUAAUUGGAGGCAAUCCCAGGAUGCAGGAGAGAGGGGAUGGAGCCACAGCAGGUCUGGGGAAGGGAGAGAAGCCGGCCCCGAGACCGCAGCCCGAGGACCCAUUCAGGCCAGCAGUGCCUUCUGUGCACUUCCACAAGGUCACACGUUCUUCCAAAGUUGCCAUCAUGGAGAGAUAGGCUUCCACGUAGUCUUGACUCCACUGGAUUUCAGUCCUUAGGUGACUUUUCCUGUGAUCACACUCAGCCCUGAUACAGUCAUUGCUGGGGCCUCCCCUGGCUGGACGUUCCGCUUUUGGUUCACAUUCUUUCCUCCUGCCCCGAGACUGGCCAUGGGCCUCCCAAAGGCUAGCUGGGAGGACCUCCCUUCCACGGCUGUGCUCUUGCUCUGCCCAUGCUGUCGCCUCCAUCUCCACCUCCCUCUCCAUCCUCACCACCAGCCCUCGAGUCAGUGGGGAGCUUUCCACUCACCAAGCCCAGGCAAGUGCAUCGCGUGAAUUUCUCUUGCGCCUCCCACUAGAGGUAGAGGCGCUGUUGUCACCCUAUCUGCUGAGGAUAUGCUGGGGCUGGCAGGGGCCACCCAAGACCAAGGGUGUCACUGUCUCCAUCCUGUGCCCACCCAGUCCUGCCCCCUGGGCUCCCUUCAAAUCUUUUUUUUUUUUUUUUUUUGAGACAGAGUCCUGCUCUGUCUCCCAGGCUGCAGUGCAGUGGUACAAUCUCAGCUCACUGCAAUCUCUGCCUCCUGGGUUCAAGCGAUUCUCCUGCCUCAGCCUCCCAAACUGCUGGGACUACAGGCACCCACCACCACACCCGGCUAAUUUUUUAUUUUUAUUUUUGUAUUUUUAGUAGAGAUGAGGUUUCACUAUGUUGGCCAGGCUGGUCUUGAACUCCUGACCUCGUGAUCCCCCUGCUGCAGCCUCCCAAAGUGCUAGGAUUACAGGCGUGAGCCACCACACCUGGCCCCCUUCAAAUCUUAACAGAGAAGCCACCAAAGUCUCCUUGGGUCCAUCACAUGGAUGGGCCUCCUGGGCCCCUCAGACCCUGGGCUUCCCUUGAGGUCCUGGAGCUAUGUGGGCUCCAGCUCUGGGAAGGUGGACCCCCAUGCAUGUGUCCUGCCGUCACUGUCUCUAUGGAGUCUGGCUCACACUAAGUGAGCCAUAAGGCCUUCUUCAAGGUCAUCUGUCCCACUGAUUUCAGACUCAGGGCGGAGUGUGAAAUCAUCUGUCCCCCACAGUGCACUCAGAACCCUGUCUGGACUAGGGCACACACACAUGCAUGCGCAUAUGAACACACAUAUGCAUAUGCACGCACACAUGCAAGGCUGCAAGUCUCAUGCACACACACAUGCACACACAUGCACAUGCAUGUUCACAUGCAGAGGCACUCAGGCACCUAGAGCCUUCUCAUCCUGCACUUUGAGUCCCCCCUCCCCUUGCCCAUCCUUGCCCAUCCUUCAAGGCCUCAGUCAAAAGCCAUCUUUUACAAAUUGUCUCUGGUUGACUUUCCUUU